AUGAUUGGCCGCUGGAGGUAGGCGGGAUUUCCGGGCACGGCUUCCGGCGUCCUUCCCUCUCAGGGUAGCUCCAGCUGUCCCUCCCGCAGUUGGCCCUGUGGUGUUCCGAAGCCGGUUACGUACGCCUGAGGGCCAGGCGAACCUCAGGCUCUUUGUCCUACUAAAAAGCGCAGCACAAUGGUAGAAGCAGAUCAUCCUGGCAAGCUUUUCAUUGGUGGCCUCAAUAGAGAAACCAAUGAGAAGAUGCUUAAAGCAGUAUUUGGGAAACAUGGUCCCAUAUCAGAAGUUCUUUUGAUAAAGGAUCGAACCAGCAAAUCCAGAGGCUUUGCAUUUAUUACUUUUGAGAACCCUGCAGAUGCUAAGAAUGCUGCGAAAGAUAUGAAUGGAACGUCUUUGCAUGGAAAAGCAAUAAAAGUAGAACAAGCCAAGAAACCAUCUUUUCAAAGUGGUGGUAGGCGGAGACCACCAGCUUCUUCGAGAAACAGAAGCCCUUCAGGAAGUCUGAGAUCUGCAAGAGGAAGCAGUGGAGGAACAAGAGGGUGGCUUCCCUCACAUGAAGGGCACCUGGAUGAUGGUGGAUACACUCCUGAUCUCAAGAUGAGUUAUUCUAGGGGACUCAUUCCAGUUAAAAGAGGUCCAUCUUCAAGAAGUGGAGGUCCUCCUCCGAAAAAAUCUGCUCCUUCUGCUGUGGCAAGAAGCAAUAGUUGGAUGGGAAGCCAAGGUCCCAUGUCACAAAGAAGAGAGAAUUAUGGAGUUCCUCCACGCAGAGCGACAAUAUCUUCCUGGAGAAAUGAUCGCAUGUCAACAAGACAUGAUGGUUAUGCAACUAACGAUGGAAAUCAUCCAAGUUGCCAAGAAACGAGGGAUUAUGCUCCACCAUCUAGAGGCUAUGCAUACCGUGAUAAUGGUCAUUCUAAUCGGGAUGAACAUUCCUCUAGAGGAUAUAGAAAUCAUCGAAGUUCCCGAGAAACUAGGGAUUAUGCUCCACCAUCUAGAGGCCAUGCAUACCGUGAUUAUGGUCAUUCUCGUCGGGAUGAAAGUUAUUCUAGAGGAUACAGAAAUCAUCGAAGUUCCCGAGAAACUAGGGAGUAUGCUCCACCAUCUAGAGGCCAUGGAUACCGUGAUUAUGGUCAUUCUCGUCGACAUGAAAGUUAUUCUAGAGGAUAUAGAAAUCAUCCAAGUUCCCGAGAAACCAGGGAUUAUGCUCCACCACAUAGAGACUAUGCAUACCGUGAUUAUGGUCAUUCUAGUUGGGAUGAACAUUCCUCUAGAGGAUAUAGUUAUCAUGAUGGCUACGGUGAGGCCCUUGGUAGAGAUCAUUCUGAACAUCUAAGUGGAAGUUCUUAUAGAGAUGCACUUCAGAGAUACGCGUCUCGCUCUGGUGCCCAGGCUGGAGCACAGUGGUGUGAUCUCACUUUACUGCAAACUCCAUCACCAGGGUUCAAUGGAUUCUCCUGCAUCAGCCUUCCAAGUAGCUGGGAUAACAUCCACGGGCCACCAAGCUUGGCUAGCUUUGCUGAAAGUUGAUUCUCACCCUAAUUCAGCAAUCAGGGUGUCAUCCUCAAGAGACUAUCACCUUGCUUUGGAUUGUGACCUCUGACUCCACCACUUUCAUCCUAUAGCAGUCCUACCUUUGUGUAUUUAAUCAACUUUGUACAUGGUUAAAAAAAUAAAAGUGCAGUGAAAUGUCAGGCCAUGCUGUGAAAUGUUCCAGUGUUUCUAUAUCUCAAAUUGACCUUUCAUGUUAUAGAAGAUAAGAAAAACAAUUCAUUUCUUAGUAUUCAGUCCAAUGCACCCUUUCUUAUUAAUAUGCCAAACCUGUCCCUUCAAGGCACUGACAUCCAAGCACAGCUAGACGUAUCAAAAUUUAUUCUCAACAAUAACCAUUAUGUUAAUAACUGUUGCCCAGAUCUGGACCCUGCCUGUGAAAUCUUUGGUUAGAAGUUGCUAUAAUGGCUCAAGCUAGGGGAAUGACUAUUUUUUUUGGCAUAAUUACUGCUGUCAUCUUACUGAAAAAAUAUCACAUUAGAUGACAGCUUUUAGUUAGAUCAAUUCUGUUGAUUCAUUUUUAAUGUCUAUCAUUUAUGAUAUUGCACAAGUAAAGAUCUUUGAUAACUUAAAUGGUUAACUGAGAAAUGACUAAAAUAACUCACAGCAAUUCAAACAUUCAUUUACUUACUAGAAGUGCCAUACAUCAUUAACUUCAGAUGAAAACAAAGUUGGGAAAUUGUGAGUGCUAAAUUGCUUACUAAAGUAUGUAUUUCAGGGUAUUUUAUAAAACUAUCCAUGCCACGUAUGAUGCUUCACCAGCAAGGAUAAAGCUUUAGCCUAUAUAAAAAAUAGUCUUUGGUUCUUAAUACAUCUGUACAUUUGUCUCCAUAGCCUCAAAACAAGUCACCCAUGUACUUGACUUUCAGCUGAGUUGACUACCAGUUAUUAGGAUUUAAGCAAACAGAAUAAAGAUUUCAAAAUCUGGUGACCAAAUAUGAGAAAUCACACUCUCACCAUAAGUAAUAAUUAUUCUCAAGUGCCACUGCAAAUGCAAAACUGAAAGAAGAAAUUAAGUCUAAUAUAUUGCAAUAUUCUAAAAUCUAAAAUUUCCUCUUUGAGGUCUGGUUGUUCAUGCCUGGAAUUGCAGCUCUCUGGGAGGCUUAGAAGGGAGGACUGCUUCAAACCCAGAGUUUGACAGCAGCAUAGGCAACACAGCAAGAACCAUUUUUAAAAUGUAACUAAAUAUUUAAUUAGUUAAAUUGGGCAUGAUGGCACACAUCUGUUGUUCCACUUAGGAGUUCACAGUUGUAGUUUGCUGUUAUCACACACUGCAUUUCAGCCUGGGCCAUGAGGCAAGACUUUGUCUCUACAAAAUAAUUCAAUAUAAAAAACAAAAUAAAUUAAAAUAAAAACACUUUCAGGUGUUUUUUGGAAGUUUGUAUAAUUGCUCUAAAAGUAGAGACAUUGUUUAAAGUUGAGCAGUCAAUGGGGGAGUGGAGAGUGAUUGUUUAUAUUGUUUUCCAGAAAUU